GGCUCGCGGCUCCCCGGGACCCCCACGGGGCCGCGUGAGGCGGGGAGGCCGGCGCCCGGGCUGUGUUCCCUGUGGAACCCACGGGGCCUUCUCGUACCCUGGCCCGGCGUGCGUCCUCCUGCGCUGAACCGGGAGCGCUCGGGUGGGACUCAGGGAGCCUUGAUCACUUCCCGCCUGCGUCCCGGACCCGGUGGAGGAGCGCUCCUUUCUGCCUCGCCGGGGGUCGCGGCCUACGCCGCCGACCCCACUGUCCCCGCCACUCUCCGACAGCGGCGCGGGAAGCCCUUCGAGAAAAGCGGCGGCGGCCAGGCCUCAGCGAUUUCCUUCUCGGGCCCCUGGGCUGCGGCAGUUGUGAGGAGAGCUCAGAACAGCCUCCCUCCCCCACAACCAGCGCAUUCAUGGAUUCCUUGUAAUUUUCCCAACUACCCUGUGAGCUAUAUGUCUUUGGCUUUCAAGAUCUUCUUUCCACAAACCCUCCGUGCACUCAGCCGAAAAGAACUGUGCCUAUUCCGAAAACAUCACUGGCGUGAUGUAAGACAAUUCAGCCAGUGGUCAGAAACAGAUCUGCUUCAUGGACAUCCCCUCUUCCUGAGAAGAAAGCCUGUUCUAUCAUUCCAGGGAAGCCAUCUAAGAUCACGUGCCACCUACCUUGUUUUCUUGCCAGGGUUGCAUGUGGGACUCUGCAGUGGCCCCUGUGAGAUGGCUGAGCAACGGUUCUGUGUGGACUAUGCCAAGCGUGGCACAGCUGGCUGCAAAAAAUGCAAGGAAAAGAUUGUGAAGGGCGUAUGCCGAAUUGGCAAAGUGGUGCCCAAUCCCUUCUCAGAGUCUGGGGGUGAUAUGAAAGAGUGGUACCACAUUAAAUGCAUGUUUGAGAAACUAGAGCGGGCCCGGGCCACCACAAAAAAAAUCGAGGACCUCACAGAGCUGGAAGGCUGGGAAGAGCUGGAAGAUAAUGAGAAGGAACAGAUAACCCAGCACAUUGCAGAUCUGUCUUCUAAGGCAGCAGGUACACCAAAGAAGAAAGCUGUUGUCCAGGCUAAGUUGACAACCACUGGCCAGGUGACUUCUCCAGUGAAAGGCGCCUCAUUUGUCACCAGUACCAAUCCCCGGAAAUUUUCUGGCUUUUCAGCCAAGCCCAACAACUCUGGGGAAGCCCCCUCGAGCCCCACCCCUAAGAGAAGUCUGUCUUCAAGCAAAUGUGACCCCAGGCAUAAGGACUGUCUGCUACGGGAGUUUCGAAAGUUAUGCGCCAUGGUGGCCGAUAAUCCUAGCUACAACACGAAGACCCAGAUCAUCCAGGACUUCCUUCGGAAAGGCUCAGCAGGAGAUGGUUUCCACGGUGAUGUGUACCUAACAGUGAAGCUGCUGCUGCCAGGAGUCAUUAAGACUGUUUACAACUUGAACGAUAAGCAGAUUGUGAAGCUUUUCAGUCGCAUUUUUAACUGCAACCCAGAUGAUAUGGCACGGGACCUAGAGCAGGGUGACGUGUCAGAGACAAUCAGAGUCUUCUUUGAGCAGAGCAAGUCUUUCCCCCCAGCUGCCAAGAGCCUCCUUACCAUCCAGGAAGUGGAUGAGUUCCUUCUGCGGCUGUCCAAGCUCACCAAGGAGGAUGAGCAGCAACAGGCCCUACAGGACAUUGCCUCCAGGUGUACAGCCAAUGACCUUAAAUGCAUCAUCAGGUUGAUCAAACAUGAUCUGAAGAUGAACUCAGGUGCAAAACAUGUGUUAGACGCCCUUGACCCCAAUGCCUAUGAAGCCUUCAAAGCCUCGCGCAACCUGCAGGAUGUGGUGGAGCGGGUCCUUCACAACGCGCAGGAGGUGGAGAAGGAGCCGGGCCAGAGACGAGCUCUGAGCGUCCAGGCCUCGCUGAUGACACCUGUGCAGCCCAUGUUGGCGGAGGCCUGCAAGUCCGUUGAGUAUGCAAUGAAGAAAUGUCCCAAUGGCAUGUUCUCUGAGAUCAAGUACGAUGGAGAGCGAGUCCAGGUGCAUAAGAAUGGAGACCACUUCAGCUACUUCAGCCGCAGUCUCAAGCCCGUCCUUCCUCACAAGGUGGCCCACUUUAAGGACUACAUUCCCCAGGCUUUUCCUGGGGGCCACAGCAUGAUCUUGGAUUCUGAAGUGCUUCUGAUUGACAACAAGACAGGCAAACCACUGCCCUUUGGGACUCUGGGAGUACACAAGAAAGCAGCCUUCCAGGAUGCUAAUGUCUGCCUGUUUGUUUUUGAUUGUAUCUACUUUAAUGAUGUCAGCUUGAUGGACAGACCUCUGUGUGAGCGGCGGAAGUUUCUUCAUGACAACAUGGUUGAAAUUCCAAACCGGAUCAUGUUCUCAGAAAUGAAGCGAGUCACAAAAGCUUUGGACUUGGCUGACAUGAUAACCCGGGUGAUCCAGGAGGGAUUGGAGGGGCUGGUGCUGAAGGAUGUGAAGGGUACAUAUGAGCCUGGGAAGCGGCACUGGCUGAAAGUGAAGAAAGACUAUUUGAACGAGGGGGCCAUGGCCGACACAGCUGACCUGGUGGUCCUUGGAGCCUUCUAUGGGCAAGGGAGCAAAGGCGGCAUGAUGUCAAUCUUCCUCAUGGGCUGCUACGACCCUGGCAGCCAGAAGUGGUGCACAGUCACCAAGUGUGCAGGAGGCCAUGAUGAUGCCACGCUUGCCCGCCUGCAGAAUGAACUAGACAUGGUGAAGAUCAGCAAGGACCCCAGCAAAAUACCCAGCUGGUUGAAGGUCAACAAGAUCUACUAUCCUGACUUCAUCGUCCCAGACCCAAAGAAAGCUGCCGUGUGGGAGAUCACAGGGGCUGAAUUCUCCAAAUCGGAGGCUCAUACAGCUGACGGGAUCUCCAUCCGAUUCCCUCGCUGCACCCGAAUCCGAGAUGAUAAGGACUGGAAAUCUGCCACUAACCUUCCCCAACUCAAGGAACUGUACCAGUUGUCCAAGGAGAAGGCAGACUUCACUGUAGUGGCUGGAGAUGAGGGGAGCUCCACUACAGGGGGUAGCAGUGAAGAGAAUAAGGGUCCCUCAGGGUCUGCUGUGUCCCGCAAGGCCCCCAGCAAGCCCUCAGCCAGUACCAAGAAAGCAGAAGGGAAGCUGAGUAACUCCAACAGCAAAGAUGGCAACAUGCAGACUGCAAAGCCUUCCGCUAUGAAGGUGGGGGAGAAGCUGGCCACAAAGUCUUCUCCAGUGAAAGUAGGGGAGAAGCGGAAAGCUGCUGAUGAGACGCUGUGCCAAACAAAGGUAUUGCUGGACAUCUUCACUGGGGUGCGGCUUUACUUGCCACCCUCCACACCAGACUUCAGCCGUCUCAGACGCUACUUUGUGGCAUUCGACGGGGACCUGGUACAGGAAUUUGAUAUGACUUCAGCCACGCACGUGCUGGGUAGCAGGGACAAGAACCCUGCGGCCCAGCAGGUCUCCCCAGAGUGGAUUUGGGCAUGUAUCCGGAAACGGAGACUGGUAGCUCCCUGCUAGGUUUGCUGUCUUCCCUCUCCCUCAGGCCAUACUCUCCUUUACCAUACUACUGGACUGGACUCAGGCUGGAGGCAGAUAGACACAGUAUAGGGGGAAUGGGCUUGCUUCUCCCAAACCCACCAGUUCUCCACUGUCUCUUCUGGACCAGGAAUUAGUUGCUGUGGGUGCCACAGCUGAAGUCAGUUUGUCUUGCUGGUUUAAAUAGAUCUUUCAGAGCUGGGUGCUGGGUUUGCCAUCUUUUUGUUUUCUUUGAAAAGCAGCUUAGUUACCCUUUUUAUAAAUAAAAUAUCUUGCAGUUAUCUUUGUCCUUUCCCCACCUACACCCCCAAUAAUUUCCCUAGAGAUUAAGGAGUAAAGGCUGGGCUAUGGCAGCUCUGUCCACAAAGCCUUCUCUCCCAUCCUUGCCUGUUCCUUUGUACUUCCAGGCUCAUUUUAAAGUUGUAUUUAAAGGACUGCCCUCGGAAAUGCUUCUGUUUAGCGGAACUUGUAUUCAGCCUGACACGCUUUGCCAGGAACAAACCUCAUGUGAAAGAAAACAAAAUGAAUUUUUUUACUUUCUUCUCUGUGUUCUCCUAUUACAUGGUGAGGAUCCCCAGUUUGAAGGGAGGGGACUAGGGUCAGGUAGGAAAAUGGGGCCUUUAUGAAGAAAGGGGAGGUUAUUUGGGCCACUCCUCUGGAGGGAUAGAGGGCUCCAGGAAGAUCUGCAUCCCCAAAACCUGGAAACAAGACUGUUCUUUAAGAAUAAAAAUCCACAUGGGGCUUGAGGCCAAGAACAGCCCUUGUUGCCACCAACAUGGAGACUUUGUACCAUAUCCCAUUCUUAGUGCUCGAGUGUUCCAACCUGAAGUUGAAGAAGCCACCCUGGCUGCACAUGCCAUCAGCCAUGACUGUGUAUGCUCUGGUGGUGGUGUCUUACUUCCUCAUGACUGGAGGAAUAAUUAUAUGAUAUUGUUGAACCCCCAAGUAUUGGCUGAUGAACGUGGGCAUCAGAGGCCAGUAGCUUUCUUGGCCUACAAAGUAAAUGGACAGUAUAUUAUGGAAGGAUUUGCAUCCAGCUUCCUGUUUACAAUGGGAGGUUUAGGUUUCAUAAUGCUGGACCAGUCGAAUGCACCAAAUAUCCCAAAACUCAAUCGAUUUUUUUUCUUCUAUUCAUUGGAUUCGUCUGUGUCCUACUGAGUUUUUUCAUGGCUGGAGUAUUCAUGUGAAUGAAACUGCCGGGCUAUCUGAUGGGUUAGAGCGCCUUUAAGAAGAAAUCAGUGGAUACUGGAUUUGCUCCUGUCAAUGAAGUUCUAAAGGCUGUACCAAUCCUCCAAUAUGAAAUGUGGGAAAGAAUGAAGAGCAGCAGUAAAAGAAAUACCUAGCGAAAAAAACAGGAAGCAUAUUGAAGCUCGGACUAGAAUUUCUUCUUGGUAUCAGAGAGACAAGUUUAUCACAGUAUUUUUUUUUUUCCUGCUGACCUAUUGAUAAUACCAACAAUGUUGAGUGGCAUUUUCUUCUUAGUUUUUAAUUUCUUAAAGAAAAUAUACUCCAUAUCUGCAGGGAAAAAAAUAAAAAUCCACACCUGAGAACAGAUCCAUACAACCUGCUUACAAAGAACAGCUCCUGUGCUACCUGAGGCUGAUUUAUUUGAAGAACAAAAGGAAGAGAGACAAUUUAGUGUAGACAAGUGCUAUUCAAUAGAACUUUUUGCAGCAGUGGAAAUAUCCAUAAAUCUGCAGUAUCCAACCAAACUAGCCACAGACAGCUGCUGAGCAAUUGAAAUGAAGCUGGCACAACUAAGGAACUGAAGUUCUUAUUUUAAUUCAACUUCAAAUGGUCACAUGUCACUAGUGACUACCACACUGGACAGUGCAGGUGUAGACGGAGUUCAGAUCAGACUCCUGAAACUUAAUGGCUCUAACCUUAGGCAAGUUACGUUAACAUCUAAGCCUCAAUCCCUCCAAGUAGAAUGGGUGCACCUAAAUCAUAGGGUUGUCCUGUUGUCCUGAGCAACAUUAUGUAAAGCACUUAGCCCAGAGCCUAGCACAUAGUUAUCUAGAGUUGGGAACGUCACUCCUGGUGUGCAUGUCCAGACCCUACCCGGGAGAAGGGCCUAACCUAUGACUUUAGAACCCUCAGUUGCAGGUGUGCAUGUUCCAGCCAACACUCCACUCUGAGUGCAGGCUCAUCAGGACACCAUAUGGUUGUAAACUGGCUGCCAUGUCCCAAUCCUUCCAGCUCUUGAGGGUCAGUUCUCACCUUAUGAACAAAUUAACAGGCUCUGGACCUAUAAGAUCAAGGACCACUGCGCCCCCUGGCCACCCCACCGCCCCCCCCCAACUUUGAUCUGAUUGACUUUGGCUUCCACCUACUGUUUAAAAUGUGUAUGUUGGGGGAGUAGGGACAGCACGGGGGAGGGGUUUACUUUCCUGACUCUAGCCCAGGACAUUUGGUGUUUUUGAAUAGGCACCAUUCAGCCUUGCUUCAGUAUUAGGAAUAAGAUACUUUUUAUUCCAUCCUCUAUGGAGACAAAAAGCUGCUCCUCCUUUGAGUACUGACCUACAUAGAUUUCCAUUUCUCUCUUCAGCCUCAGGCCAAACAAACAACCGGACAGGGCAGCAGAACAAGGCUGUCUCCUCAGGAUCCUGCCAAAGGCACUGUCCUCUCCAACCUGGACCCAGCCCCACUUGCCCUUAUUGGUUGCUUACACCCAGAGUGCACACUCACAGGAAAGGGCCUCUGCUGGCUGCAGGUGAUCAUCUUGUCCCUUCUCUGCCUUAGUGUGUGUUAUUGCCAUUUCAAUGUCAGUGGUUUUUUAUGUAUUUUCUUCCAGUCUUUGCUGCUGAGAUCUGACUGUAUAUACUAUUUUGUAUCCUUUCAUGUAUUUCUUUCAUGUAUUUCAAUGCAGCCCUCAACAUCAUCAUCAUAAAUCUCUCCAGCAGAAUGCUGGAGGCCUCCCUCUUCUGAACCUCUACAUGCUGCUGGCUGGCAUCAAGCAGAGGUCAUCACUGGGUGCUGAACAGGUCAGCUCCCUAGGGCAAUGUGAGCAAAGUGUUGUGGCUCAUCCUCGAUCCUUUAUGCCCUUUUGGCAAGAUUCCUUUCUCUUCUCAGUCACAGCAGAUGGACACAUAAUCUUGUUCUCCCAGGGGCUGCAUUCUCAGUAGUCUUUUCCCUGCUCCUUGGGCGCCUGGUCAGGGAGGUUUGUACAAGCCUGCGCACACACAGCAGUCUGUCACGAGGCUGGGCCAACCUUUUUUUUUUUUUUAAACAGACUCUUGCUCUGUCAUUCAGGCUGGAGUGCAGUGGUGCAAUCUCAGCUCACUGCAACCUCUGCUUCCCGGGUUCACAAGCAAUUCUCAUGCCUCAGCCUCCCAAGUGGCUAAGACUUAACAAACAGGCACACACCAUCACUCGCAGCUAAGUUUUUGUAUUUUUAGUAGAGACCACGUUUCGCCAUGUUGUCCAGACUGGUCUCAAACUCCUGGCCUCGAGUCAUCCACGCACCUCAGCCUCCCAAAGUGCUGGGAUUACAGGCGUGAGCCAUGGCGCCCAGCCUGGGCCAACCUUUUCUGAGCCAUAGUCCAGCUGUACUACAGCUGUAUCCAAAAGGUACCAUGUAUCUCCCAGGGUAACCUGAAGACCUAACUGGGCAUACUAACUGUCCUCAGAUUUCAGUUCUUUAAGGCCCAUCUCUUCUAGAUCAGUGUAAAUAUCUGAACUCACUUGGUGCUUCAACCCAAUUGGUCUUGGGAUUCAUCCUUUACCUACCCAGCUCUCAUUCUCUUCUAGGUUGUUCCAUGGCCUCUUCCAUAUAUUACAUUUGUGGUCUUGAGCAAGUUAGUUAGUUACAACAACACUGAGCAUCUUGACCAAGGUCACUUGGCCCAACCACAGGCUAAUCCCAGGCCAUGUGCACAUCCCAGGAUUAGCUUGUGGUUUAUCAGUUGUCAAUUUUUUUUUUUUUUUAAUACAGGGUCUCACUCUGUCACCCUGGCUGGAGUGCGGUGGCGAUCAGAGCUCACUGCAGCUUCAAUCUCCUGGCUCAAGUGAUCCUCCCACCUCAGCCUUCCAAGUAGUUGGGACUACCCACAUGCACCACCAUGCACGGCUAAUUUUUUGGUUUUUUUGGGUUUUUUGUUUGUGUUUUUUUUUGUUUUGUUUUUUGAGACAGAGUCUCGCUCUUUCGCCCAGGCCGGACUGCAGUGGCGCAAUCUUGGCUCACUGCAAGCUCCGCCUCCCGGGUUCACACCAUUCUCCUGCCUCAGCCUCCCGAGUAGCUGGGACUACAGGCACCCGCCACCACGCCUGGCUAAUUUUUUGUAUUUUUAGUAGAGACGGGGUUUCACCGUGUUAGCCAGGGUGGUCUCGAUCUCCUGACCUCGUGAUCUGCCCGCCUCAGCCUCCCAAAGUGCUGGGAUUACAGGCGUGAGCCACCGCACCCGGCCCUUGUUUGUUUUUUUAAGUAGAGACAAGGUCUCACUACAUUGCCCAGGUUGGUCUCAAACUCCUGAGCUCAAGCAGUCUUCCCACCUUGGCCUCCUAAAGUGUGGAAAUUAUAGCAUGAACCACUGUCAGGCUCUUUUGUCAGUCCUAUCAACCUCUAACAUCCUCGCACCAGACAGGACAGGUGUCUGUAUUGAAACUUUAUUACAAAAUUAUAAAGCAGAGCUCUGUAACAAAAUAAUACACAUUUGGGUUUGCUUUAACCUCCAAGUAAGUCUGAGAAAAUCUUAAUAAAAGCCACUUGAAGUAACAAUUCACAUCCAAGAGAUUUCCACAAAUUUAUACAAUGUAUAUUGAGCACUAGUUCCUGUACAGCUUAUUCUUAUUAGUUUGGAUCCAACUAUUCCAAUGUAUUAUGAACCAGUCAGCUAUCUGUCUUUUGAAACAAGUCUUAACUGAAAUCUCAGAGUAAUCAGCAAAAGCUACGGAAUAAUUCUAAGAAUUAGAUGUUUCCAUAUCAUUAAAACCAAGGAUCCAUGAGGGGCAGAAGGGAGGAUUCAAAGAUUUAAAAAAAAUCAAAUUUUAGACCUUGGUUAAAUAUUAACUGGAAUGGGAUCUUGGAACUCCCAACUUUAAUUUGGUGUAAUAAAAAUGAUGCAAAAAAAAAAAAAAUCAGGGUUGUUUGACACCUUUUUUCCUAAAGGGAAACCUUCACCAAAAGGGGAUAAAAGAUUUAAAGGCAAAAUGAGUAAACAACCUCAGUUUUAAUUCUUACUGAGGUUACUAACCAGCUAUCAGUAUAUUAUUUUCGAUUU